AGUCCCGUGUGUGCUGCGGCCCCGUCUCUCUCCCUCUCUGAGUGACACUGUCUGCCCUGCUGCUUGCCGUCCCGCUGUUGGCACCGCUUUAGACCCCAUAUUUCCCAGCGGUCACCGUGCUCAUUUUUGGCUUCCAGCUACCGUUUUUCUUAGGUUACCCCGCGUAGCUGGCCCGUCCUUCCUUCUCCUGUCUCUUCUGUGCCUACCGCGGGGGGUUCCCUUACCAAGGUCUCCAUCACCCCCAGGCCCACCUCCCUCGGGCCCCUCUCUGCCCUUGCCCUCCACCUCAGCGACUCCGUGGGGCUUUUGUGAUCCCAGCUGCAGUUAGCGAGCGCCCCUGUGUGCUCAGAGACACGCCAGUGAGCCGGGAAGGACAGAGACCCAAGUCCCAUCCCUCUGGGGCCCCCUUGGAAUGGGGGAGGCGAACAGGAAACCACCACAGUGAGUGUUGGGGUGCCCCGCAGGCGACGGUGCUGAGAAAAAGAGAGUGGGGUUGGGGGCAGUGCGUGCGCAGGCUGGCGGGUGGGCGAGGCGGGUGGAGGAUGCGUGGGGCGCAGUGCUUGCGCGCAGUGGGUGGCGGGGUGGACGAGGUGAGGGCCUGGCCAGGUGGGUGCCUGCGUGUCCAGCCUGAGGGGCGGCCCACGCAGCAGCCUCUGGGAGCCCUGGGGCCUUCCGUGGGCUGCUUCCUGUGGCGUCCUGCGGGCUGGCCGCCCCUCGGUGGGCUCCGGUGCUGGCCUCUGCCUUCCCCAGGGCCACGGUGGGCUCCUAGUGGCCUUUCUUCCCUCUCCAUCAACAUCCUUGUCCCAGGAAGAGGCGUCCACUGCCUGCUACACGCCACCCAGCCGUGUUCAUUUCCGUGUUCCAGUGUCACCCGUGUGCCUAGAACGUUCCUGGCACAGAAAAGCCACGCAGAAAACAGCUGCUGGGCCAACACCGAGACCCCAGGUCAUUAGUGUUAAUCAGAGUGAUGAAGAGGUUGCCAUUGGCAAUUCGGAAGGGAAUUCAGGGAGAGCAGCCGCAGUGCCCUGUCCCCAGAGCCUGGUGUCCAGAGCCAGAGUUCCGAGGGCCUCCUCAUAGUUUUAAAACUCUUUAUUUUAUUUUUAUUUUUUAUUUUUGAGACAGAGUCUCACUGUGUUGCUCAGGCUGGAGUGCAGUGGCUUGAUCUUGGCUCACUGCAUCCUCUGCCUCCUAGGUGCAAGCAGUUCUCUUGCCUCAGACUCCUGAGUAGCUGGGAUUUGUGCCACGACGCCCGGCCAGUUUUUUUUUUUUUUUUUUUUUUUUUUAGUAGAGAUGGGGUUUCACCAUAUUGGCCAGGCUGGUCUCGAACUCCUGACCUCAGAUGAUCCGCCCACCUCUGCUUCCCAAAGUGCUGGGAUUGCAGGUAUGUGCCACCACGCCCAGCCCUGAAACUACUUUCAUUUUAAAACGAUGAGUUCCUAAGAACUAGACUCUGAUCCCUGGAAACAACAUGCCAACCUCUGGCAUGCAGGACCUUUGCUUUCCAGGCAGGCAUUUCCCAAUUUUGUUAGAUUCUCAAGGGAGCCCCUGCCCCUGCUAAAGUUAAGACUCCUGUGCUGGGACAGGCAGGCUCCUCUGAUGUGGCUGCACGGGCGCACUCAGCAGCCUCGAUACAAUUUGAACUUCUUGCUGACAUUUGAACACAGAGGACGGCACAUACAUCCCCACAUUUCCCCACUUUUUUGGAAGUCUCGUGACUCCUGGCCUGCUGGUUUCCCGAGGACCGCUUCUGCUGGAGCGAUGGCCACUUGGGGAGGGUCGGUGCUCUCCACUGGCCUGAGUUGCUGGGCCCAUCACUGCUGCGUCGAAGCCUGAGACCACCCCACCCGGUCCCAAGGAGGACACAGGCUUUUCUGGUUUGGUUGAGACUUGCAGAGCCUAAAGAAAACUGCUGAGUUGUUUUUGCGAGUUACCUAAUGGUGCUUUAGCUGCUGCAUGCUUUUGUCCCAUGGUGCGUUUGUUUGUAAUUCACCACAGCUGUAAUUGCAGCAGAGCCAGAGAGCUUUCUCCUUAUUACAUAUCCUGAGAAGGAAGCCCUGGCAGCCCGACCUGAGAGAGGGUGAUGUGGCUCACUCAUGCAGGGAUGCUGGGACAUCAGGCUGGGAGUCAAGAGAUGGAAUUUUAGGCUUUCUCUGCCACCUUUUACCUUUGUAACUAGGGUUGAUGUGUGAACCCUUUGGGCAGAUUAAUCAUUAGUUGCCUCUUUAAACCAAUCUUUUAUUUAUUUAUCUUUAUUUAUUUAUUUUUGAGACAAGGUCUCACUCUGUCACCCAGGCUGGAGUGGGUGCAGUGGCGCUAUUUCGGCUCAGUGCAACCUCUACCUCUUGGGUUCAAGUGAUUCUCAUGCCUCAGCCUCCCAGGUAGCUUGGAUUACAGGCGCCUGCCACCACGCCUGUCUCAUUUUUUAAUUUGUAUUUUUAGUAGAGACAGGGUUUUGCUAUGUUGGCAAGGCUGGUCUCGAACUCCUGACCUCAAAUGAUCCAUCUGCCUCGGCCUCCCAAAGUACUGGCAUUACAGGUGUCAGCCACCGCGCCUGGUCUUUAAACCAAUCCUUUAAAUCUUCUCCAUUUUCAAAGUAGAGUGGGAAGAAACUGAUUUUUCUAUGAAUAAAGAUUGUGUAAGUCGUUCUUUCAAAUGUGAUUUGUGUUCACAUUCAGAAAUUUGUUAGUGACAUAUUUUCACUUAUUUGCAAGUGCCUUUCCUUACAGUUUUUCUGCCACUCAACUCAGAUGAGUUAUUCUCAAGGAUAAAGACCACUUAGAUGAAUAUAUUUUCAAAUUCUUACUCUGAAUGUGUUUAAGUAACCACCCUCUACCCCGUUUGGCAAAAUGUUUCCCAUUUUUCUGUGGUUUUUAUUUUAUUUUUUGUGGCUUUCAGAACCAGAUCACUUCUUGGAAGGCAUAUUAGAAGUUUGCAGUUGAGACGAUAAAAUAAGUCACUUUUUCCUGGGAGGUGGUAUUAUGUCACACAUCAUUUGGUAUCAAAAUUUCCCCCGGCUGUGGCUGCAGAGUUGAAGGACAUCAGCUGGCUGCGCUUGGGGUUGGUGGUCCGUUGUGAACUCUGCACCGUAUAGUGUGUGUGCUUUAUGUGCAAACGUUUUAACAAAGACAGGUUGCUGCGGGCAAGAAGGGUUUUAACUUCUGUUCGUGUUACUUCUGCUGAGUUGGAAGGAGCACAUUUCACAGAUGAUGUCAUUGGUGGAGGCCGAGCCUGCCAGCACCUUGUCUGCGUGUGCUUUGGCUGGACGAUGGUCUACACUGGGCCCCUGUGCAGCCUCCUGCCGGGGAGCCUGUGUCCCACCUGGCUCUGCUCUGAGCCAUUCAUGUCGCCUCCAGUGGCAGCUGUAAAAUGAAACUCAUGGCCUUUGCUGUCUCUCUUGUCCUGGGUGGUGAGGAUCAAAUGAACCUUUAUUAAUGGACAUGAAAAUAACCUUGUAAUUUCAUACACUGAAAUUACACUUUUCGUACGCUUUUCAAUGUAACACAUUGUAAAGCGCUGUAAAAAUAUCUCAGGAAAGGGCUGCCAAUUUUUGUCACAUCUCAUGUGACAAAGGUAAUUUUUUUUUUUUUUUUGGCUUGGAAAGGGAACGAAAAUAAGAUCAUUUUUCCUGGUAGGAAGGUAAAAGAUUUUAAAGAGAAGGUUUGUUACAUGUGAAAAAAACGAUUUGAUCAAAGGCAUAAUUGGUUGAAUUAUGCAUUCGACAAGGAUGGAAAUUACACGUUCAACAAAGAUGUGAAGAGCGUGCAGCCUGGCAAGGCAUCUCUGUCCUUAGCGUGCCCACCCCCAAUACGGGAAGGGCAGGAGAGGCUGGCAUGAGGCACCCGUGGUCCGUGCUGUGGGCACCUCCGGGAGGCAGCCUGGGACAGGCGGGUCCUGCUCCAGAGAGAGAAGGGGCUGCCGUCCGGCAUGUCUGGGAGGCUGGGUCCUUCCUUCCCCAAGGGUUGUAUCCACAGCCCCUCUCGAUCCUCACAGCAGCCCUGUGAAGGAGCACUGUGCCAUCCUGUGACAGGGCAGCCAGGUCUCAUUGGCACUGGGUGCUGAGGGUGGUGGGUGGGCGCAGGCCUUGAUGCCUGACUCUGACCUUGUUCUCCCCGGCGUGGUCUGCACCCUGUGAAGGGUGAGUGAACGCCCUCCUGGCCCAGUUCAGCCCCAGGUUGUGCCUGUUGUCCCCACAUCGUUAAUAAUUAUCCAUAGCGUCCCCUUCACUCGCAGAAGCGUCCGAGCUUAGACAGCAGGUUCCACGGCCACUCCAACAUGCGGUCUCAAACCCAGGGCCUGCAACUCCCGCCAUGUGCCCCGUUCUGCUUGUCACCCGCCUCGCCCUGAGGAGCCUCCAGCUGCUUCAGGACUUGUCCCUGUGUCACACAUCCAGGGCAGUUGUUCACUAGCAUCCCCGCUACCCCUGAAUCCAUCUCCACGUGCGUGGGCUUGGACCUGCUUCUCUCGCCCACUUAUCUGUGUAUCUCUGAGUAGUGAGACUUCCACGUUAGCGCUGUGGGGAAGAGGCUGGGCUUGGCUCAGCUGCUGAGGGAUCAGCCGACCCCAGGUCGCUGCGGCCCUUUCAGGAGGACGUUGGGGGGCAGGAGUGGCCGGCGGCCACCUGAGAAUGGGAGUGGCACCCGAAUAUGUGGAAUACACAGAAAUUCGAGUCCGCCUGUGGCCGUCUCCACGGUCCUUUCUACCAUGAUUUCUCCAUGUCCCCUGCAACAGCGACCCAUCCCAGCCAGGAGAGGAGAACUCUGGGAGGUUGCCUGGCAGUUACAAGUGUGUUAAGUAUUGUUGCUGCGUGCUUAUCAGUUAGGCUCAGGCACAGCUACUAACUUCCAGGCAUCUCGGCAGUGUCUGGCGUUUGGCAGUCAAGUUGUGUUUAGUUUUGACUUAAAGAUUAAAAGGUUAUAGAAUACAGGAAUAAUCUACCUUUUGAAGGAAAACUUGCCAAGUUCGCCUGACCUUUGAAAUGCCAAGAAUCCCAGAGAUGUUGAAGGAAGUGCCCAGAGGAAGAUCUGGUCCACAGUGGGUAUUCAGCACACUGAUUUCUUUCCUAUAAAAAAUUAUCUGUCAGGGCCGGGCGCGGUGGCUCAUGCCUGUAAUCGCAGCACUUUGGGAGGCCGAGGCGGGCGGAUCACGAGGUCGGGAGAUCGAGACCAUCCUGGCUAACACGAUGAAACCCCGUCUUUCCUAAAAAUACAAAAAAAUUAGCUGGGCGUGGUGGCGGGCGCCUGUAGUCCCAGCUACUCGGGAGGCUGAGGCAGGAGAAUGGCGUGAACUGGGGAGGCGGAGCUUGCAGUGAGAGGAGAUCGCGCCACUGCACUCCAGCCUGGGCGACAGAGCAGGCUGUCAACACAUUUAUAACCCCAGCAAUGGACUGAGGUGUGAGUAGGUUCCGCGUCGCCCUUUUCCUCCCAGUGUUACCCCCGGCACUGUGCUUGUGUCUCGGCAUCCUGUGGAUGGGGCCUGCGGUUAUCCAGCUGGUGGUUCAUGAGCACACACAUGCCUGAGGAGAUGGAUGGAGACAGGCGUUGCUAGUAGCAGUUCCUCCUCUUGUCACAGAGUGUGCAAAAACACUCUUAAGUACAGCCUGGUGCGAUGGGUCAAGCCUGUAAUCCCAGCACUUUGGGAGGCCGAGGCGGGUGGAUCACCUGAGGUCAGGAGUUCGAGAUCAGCCUGGCCAAUGUGGAGAAAUCCUGUCUCUACUACAAAUACAAAAAUUAGCUGGGCAUCGUGGCGGGCACCUGUAAUCCCACCUACUCGGGAGGCUGAGGCAGGAGAAGCGCUUGAACCCAGGAGGCAGAGGUUGCAGUGAGCCGAGAUCGCACCUUUGCUCUCCAGCCUGGGCAACACAGUGAGAUUCUGUCUCAAAAAAAAAAAAAAAAAGAAACCACUGUAAGUACAGACACCGUAGCAACCACACGGAGGCCCCCCGCCCCGCCCCCCGCGUGUUCCAGUGGGAAGCAGAGCCUCGGAAGGCGUGCACACGGGGGGUGCGUGAUGGUGUCUCCCUCUGCCCUCAGAUGGCCAGGCCUCGGGCCCGAUGUGCCAGGGUGGGUUCUUGUGUUCCGCGGGCUUCUUGUCCCUUCUGUCUGCUGUGUUGUGCGUGCGUCUCUCUGGGUGGCCUUGGCCGGGCUUCUCUCUCUGUGAGACAGGCGCAUCUCUCAGGGCUUUCUUCGUUCUGCUGAUAUCUAUCCCCUCUCAGGACCACUCGGUUUCAAAAGCGGUAACUAAACUUGUCUAACACGUGUGCAUGAGAGGAAGGCGGCCAGAGGCAUGGGUCUGAGGGCUUUGCUUGAAGAGCGGGCGGUGUGCGUGUCUCGCAGCGCCCCCACCUCGGUGUCUCAGGGCCUUGCUGUCUUCCGCCUUUUUCCCAGCGUCUCACCAGCAAAGUGAGUUUAUGAGAAUCAUGUUAACACACAGGCUUGAUGAUUGAGAAAGCAGAUGCUGAGAAUGUGACUAUGGAAUGAAUAAUUUUCAUUAUGAAAAACUGAUACAUUGUUUACGACAUGAUUCUCUGAGAUGCUUGUUGCUGAGAUUACAAACUUAAAUGGUUUUAUUGUUAUGUAAGCACCUAGCAUCUUAGUGUGGAGCUGAACAGGUACUGCCUGUGUUUCAGAGAGCUCAGCCGCUGUUACAGAAUACUGCAGGCUGCAUGGUUUACGCAAUAGAAAUUUAUUUCUUGUAGCUCUUGAGGCUGGAAAUCAGAUCAGGGUGUCUGCAUGGUGAGGUCUGGUGAGGGGCCCUCCUGGGGGGCAGGAGGCUGUGUCCUCCCAGAGGCGGGGAGAGAACUCUCUCUCUUCCUCCUCGUAACCACACACCAAUCCUGUCUGAUUAGGACACAGACCUCAUGAUCUCAUCUAAUCUGUGCAGGAGAAGAGAAUUGGGUGGACAGCAGGACCAUCUACGUGGGACACAGGGAGCCACCUCCGGGCGCAGAGGCCUACAUCCCACAGAGAUACCCAGACAACAGGAUCGUCUCGUCCAAGUACACAUUUUGGAACUUUAUACCCAAGAAUUUAUUUGAACAAUUCAGAAGAGUAGCCAACUUUUAUUUCCUUAUCAUAUUUCUGGUGCAGUUGAUUAUUGAUACACCCACAAGUCCAGUGACAAGCGGACUUCCACUCUUCUUUGUCAUUACUGUGACGGCUAUCAAACAGGGUUAUGAAGACUGGCUUCGACAUAAAGCAGACAAUGCCAUGAACCAGUGUCCUGUUCAUUUCAUUCAGCACGGCAAGCUCGUUCGGAAACAAAGUCGAAAGCUGCGAGUUGGGGACAUUGUCAUGGUUAAGGAGGACGAGACCUUUCCCUGCGACUUGAUCUUCCUUUCCAGCAACCGGGGAGAUGGGACGUGCCACGUCACCACCGCCAGCUUGGAUGGAGAAUCCAGCCAUAAAACGCAUUACGCGGUCCAGGACACCAAAGGCUUCCACACAGAGGAGGAUAUCGGCGGACUUCACGCCACCAUCGAGUGUGAGCAGCCCCAGCCCGACCUCUACAAGUUCGUGGGUCGCAUCAACGUUUACAGUGACCUGAAUGACCCCGUGGUGAGGCCCUUAGGAUCGGAAAACCUGCUGCUUAGAGGAGCUACACUGAAGAACACUGAGAAAAUCUUUGGUGUGGCUAUUUACACGGGAAUGGAAACCAAGAUGGCAUUAAAUUAUCAAUCAAAAUCUCAGAAGCGAUCUGCCGUGGAAAAAUCGAUGAAUGCGUUCCUCAUUGUGUAUCUCUGCAUUCUGAUCAGCAAAGCCCUGAUAAACACUGUGCUGAAAUACAUGUGGCAGAGUGAGCCCUUUCGGGAUGAGCCGUGGUAUAAUCAGAAAACGGAGUCGGAAAGGCAGAGGAAUCUGUUCCUCAAGGCAUUCACGGACUUCCUGGCCUUCAUGGUCCUCUUUAACUACAUCAUCCCUGUGUCCAUGUACGUCACGGUCGAGAUGCAGAAGUUCCUCGGCUCUUACUUCAUCACCUGGGACGAAGACAUGUUUGACGAGGAGACUGGCGAGGGGCCUCUGGUGAACACGUCGGACCUCAAUGAAGAGCUGGGACAGGUGGAGUACAUCUUCACAGACAAGACCGGCACCCUCACGGAAAACAACAUGGAGUUCAAGGAGUGCUGCAUCGAAGGCCAUGUCUACGUGCCCCACGUCAUCUGCAACGGGCAGGUCCUCCCAGAGUCGUCAGGAAUCGACAUGAUUGACUCGUCCCCCAGCGUCAACGGGAGGGAGCGCGAGGAGCUGUUUUUCCGGGCCCUCUGUCUCUGCCACACCGUCCAGGUGAAAGACGAUGACAGCGUAGACGGCCCCAGGAAAUCGCCGGACGGGGGGAAAUCCUGUGUGUACAUCUCAUCCUCGCCCGACGAGGUGGCGCUGGUCGAAGGUGUCCAGAGACUUGGCUUUACCUACCUAAGGCUGAAGGACAAUUACAUGGAGAUAUUAAACAGGGAGAACCACAUCGAAAGGUUUGAAUUGCUGGAAAUUUUGAGUUUUGACUCAGUCAGAAGGAGAAUGAGUGUAAUUGUAAAAUCUGCUACAGGAGAAAUUUAUCUGUUUUGCAAAGGAGCAGAUUCUUCGAUAUUCCCCCGAGUGAUAGAAGGCAAAGUUGACCAGAUCCGAGCCAGAGUGGAGCGUAACGCAGUGGAGGGGCUCCGAACUUUGUGUGUUGCUUAUAAAAGGCUGAUCCAAGAAGAAUAUGAAGGCAUUUGUAAGCUGCUGCAGGCUGCCAAAGUGGCCCUUCAAGAUCGAGAGAAAAAGUUAGCAGAAGCCUAUGAGCAAAUAGAGAAAGAUCUUACUCUGCUUGGUGCUACAGCUGUUGAGGACCGGCUGCAGGAGAAAGCUGCAGACACCAUCGAGGCCCUGCAGAAGGCCGGGAUCAAAGUCUGGGUUCUCACGGGAGACAAGAUGGAGACGGCCGCGGCCACGUGCUACGCCUGCAAGCUCUUCCGCAGGAACACGCAGCUGCUGGAGCUGACCACCAAGAGGAUCGAGGAGCAGAGCCUGCACGACGUCCUGUUCGAGCUGAGCAAGACGGUCCUGCGCCACAGCGGGAGCCUGACCAGAGACAACCUGUCCGGACUUUCAGCAGAUAUGCAGGACUACGGUUUAAUUAUCGACGGAGCUGCACUGUCUCUGAUAAUGAAGCCUCGAGAAGACGGGAGUUCCGGCAACUACAGGGAGCUCUUCCUGGAAAUCUGCCGGAGCUGCAGCGCGGUGCUCUGCUGCCGCAUGGCGCCCUUGCAGAAGGCUCAGAUUGUUAAAUUAAUCAAAUUUUCAAAAGAGCACCCAAUCACGUUAGCAAUUGGCGAUGGUGCAAAUGAUGUCAGCAUGAUUCUGGAAGCGCACGUGGGCAUAGGUGUCAUCGGCAAGGAAGGCCGCCAGGCUGCCAGGAACAGCGACUAUGCAAUCCCAAAGUUUAAGCAUUUGAAGAAGAUGCUGCUUGUUCACGGGCAUUUUUAUUACAUUAGGAUCUCUGAGCUCGUGCAGUACUUCUUCUAUAAGAACGUCUGCUUCAUCUUCCCUCAGUUUUUAUACCAGUUCUUCUGUGGGUUUUCACAACAGACUUUGUACGACACCGCGUAUCUGACCCUCUACAACAUCAGCUUCACCUCCCUCCCCAUCCUCCUGUACAGCCUCAUGGAGCAGCAUGUUGGCAUUGACGUGCUCAAGAGAGACCCGACCCUGUACAGGGACGUCGCCAAGAAUGCCCUGCUGCGCUGGCGCGUGUUCAUCUACUGGACGCUCCUGGGACUGUUUGACGCACUGGUGUUCUUCUUUGGUGCUUAUUUCGUGUUUGAAAAUACAACUGUGACAAGCAACGGGCAGAUAUUUGGAAACUGGACGUUUGGAACGCUGGUAUUCACCGUGAUGGUGUUCACAGUUACACUAAAGCUUGCAUUGGACACACACUACUGGACUUGGAUCAACCAUUUUGUCAUCUGGGGGUCGCUGCUGUUCUACGUUGUCUUUUCGCUUCUCUGGGGAGGAGUGAUCUGGCCGUUCCUCAACUACCAGAGGAUGUACUACGUGUUCAUCCAGAUGCUGUCCAGCGGGCCCGCCUGGCUGGCCAUCGUGCUGCUGGUGACCAUCAGCCUCCUUCCCGACGUCCUCAAGAAAGUCCUGUGCCGGCAGCUGUGGCCAACAGCAACAGAGAGAGUCCAGCAGAAUGGGUGCGCACAGCCUCGGGACCGCGACUCAGAAUUCACCCCUCUUGCCUCUCUGCAGAGCCCAGGCUACCAGAGCACCUGUCCCUCGGCCGCCUGGUACAGCUCCCACUCUCAGCAGGUGACACUCGCGGCCUGGAAGGAGAAGGUGUCCACGGAGCCCCCACCCAUCCUCGGCGGUUCCCAUCACCACUGCAGUUCCAUCCCAAGUCACAGCUGCCCUAGGUCCCGUGUGGGAAUGCUCGUGUGAUGGAUGGUCCUAAGCCUGUGGAGACUGUGCACGUGCCUCUUCCUGGCCCCCAGCAGGCAAGGAGGGGGGUCACAGGCCUUGCCCUCGAGCAUGGCACCCUGGCCGCCUGGACCCAGCACUGUGGUUGUUGAGCCACACCAGUGGCCUCUGGGCAUUCGGCUCAACGCAGGAGGGACAUUCUGCUGGCCCACCCUGCGCGCUGUCAUGCAGAGGCCAUUCCCCCAGGCCUGUGUCUUCACCCACCUGCCAUCAUUGGCCUUUGCUGUCACUGGGAGAGAAGAGCCGUCCAGGGACCCAUGGUGGCCCACAUGUGGAUGCCACAUGCUGCUGUUUCCUGCUUGCCCGGCCACCACCCAUGCCCUCCAUAGGGUGAGGUGGAGCCAUGGUGGUGCGUCCUUUACUCAACAACCCUCCAAUCCGGAUGCUGUGGGAAGGGCCGGGUCACUCGGAUACCAUCAUCCCUGCGGAUGCACCGCCGUACCCUGCUCAUCUGGGAGUGGUUUCCCUGCGGUUACGUCCAAGCCCGCCUGCCCUGUGUGUUGGGGCUGGCUGAGUUUCGGUCUCCCCAUCACCGGCCGCCUCGUGGAGAAGGCAGUGCCACGUGGGAGGACAAGGCCACGCCGGCAGCUUCCAGCCCUGCCGCAGAAGUGCCAGGAUGUCCAUCAGCCACUCGCCAGGGCACGGAGCCGUCAGUCCACUGUUACGGGAGAAUGUUGAUUUCGCGGGUGCGAGGGCCGGGAGACAGAUACUUGGCUGUGAUGAGCAGACAUCCUCUGUCCCCGUGGAGGGGUCAACACCAAGGUGGUGUUCGUGCACCAGAACCUGUCUCGGGCUGACGGGGGUGGCACACAGGACACGGGUGGAUCCCAACAGGCAGCACCGCACCUCUGCCCGCCUCCCGCACUGCAGCUCCGCCCGCCGGGCUCUGCGUCCCCACGUCCCCUCGUCCCAUCCCCACGUCCCCUCAUCCCGUCACCUCGUCCCCACAUCCCCUUGCCCCGUCACCUCGUCCUCAUGUCCCCUUGUCCUGUCACCUCGUCCCCACGUCCCCUCGUCUCCUCAUCCCCACGUCCUCUCGUCCCCUUGUCCCGUCCCCACAUACCCUCGUCCCCAUGUCCCCACGCAGGGCUCUCCUUCGUCUUAGGAUCUGUCCAGCGCUGCUCUGGGUGGGUUAGCAACCCCAGGGCUGCUGUGAUAGGAAGUCCCUGUUGUUCUCCGUACUGGCAUUUCUAUUUCUAGAAAUAAUAUUUGACAUAGCCUUAAUGGUCCUUAAAGAAGACAUUUCAGUGUGAGAUUCAGACUUCAGACGCUGAAACUGCUGCCUUUCAGGAAAGCACCACCAACGCUGGAGGAGGAGCCGGCCCUCACGCCCGCCCCGCGCCACGCUGUGGAACGGGGCUCCGGCAAGUGAAACCCAGAGGGUGUUUCCGAGGUGCUCGACAGUAGGUAUUUUUGGAAGCUCAGAUUUCACCAUUUGAUUGUAUAAUCUUUUACCUAUAAAAUAUUUAUUUGAAGUAGAGGGUAAAUCAGCGGUAAGAACAGUGAACACAGUGGUUGGGAUAAAAUAAGGUGACAAACAUCACACCAAAGAUGAGGGUAGCGAGCAACUGGCUUGAGCAGACAGAACGGGGAAGACUCCACUCUGUCCCGAGGGGCCAGCCGCAGGCGUCCCCAGGGCCACCCUGCCCUGAGGUCCUUGUGUGGCCGCCCUGGCUUGGCAGCCCUGCCCACGCUGCCCCCGCAAACAAUGGUGUGUGCGUUUUUACAGCCCUUUUUAGGAACCCAAUAUGGGCAUAAAUGUAACACCUGUAGCGGGGGCAGAUUCUCUGUAUGUUCAGUUAACAAAUUAUUUGUAAUGUAUUUUUUUAGAAAUCUUAAAAUUGCCUUUGCACUGAAGUAUUUUCAUAGCUGUUUAUAUCUCUUUUAUUCAUUUAUUUAACAUACUGUCUAAUUUUAAAAAUAGGUUUUUAAAGCUUUCAUUUUUAAGUUUAUGAAAUUUUGGCCACUUUACAUUUAGAUUCUGGUGAGAGUUUUGACUGAAUGUUCCAAUCUCUGAUGAAUGCGAAUUUUCAGAUUUGAUUUUAUUCUCUACACACACCUCUUCUUUUCUUGGUAUUUCUGGUGGCAGUGAUUAGUUGAACAGCACAUUUAAGGCACGAUAAUUUGCUACACUUUUUCUUUACAAUUUGUUGCAAUUUCAUCUGCUUUCUAUGUUUCAUUGUUAAUUGCCAUCCUUCAGCCUUAAAAAUAGAAGAUUCUCACGUGAAGGUUUAGUAAGUUGGGUCCCAGCUCUGCCUGUGUGGAGAUAGUCACCAUGUACCUCUGACAACAAGUUUUAGUGUGAAAGUCACUAAACUUUUACACACUCCCAAACGUCUUUUUAAAAAUUGCUUGGGAAAUUAUUAAAUGAAUGUGCCUGAUGAUUUGAAAUAGACAAGGGGCACGAGAUAAAAAAGAAAAGGAUGAGAAGAUCCUCAGUGAAUGACGUUGCAGGGUCUUCAUGCAAUUUUCCACCUCGCAGUAGUUAGUAUUUACUUGCCUUAAACUAACUUUGAAGCAAGUAAUGUCAACUUUGAGCACUUUGUUGAGUUUUGAAAAAUCUUAUUUGUUGCUGCACAGGUUAAUAAAUUAUCAAUUUGUAAUUCAGCAUGUUGGUCAGAGACACGGUCACUGAUUCACACCCAGUCCCUGCCACAGACCGUCUCAGACACGCACAGUGGGCCUGCUGCAUGAUUCACACCCAGUCCCUGCCACAGACCGUCUCAGACACGCACAGUGGGCCUGCUGCAUGAUUCACACCCAGUCCCUGCCACAGACCGUCUCAGACACGCACAGUGGGCCUGCUGCAUGCGUGUUACCUGGCUUUUGGCUCCACGCUCACUCAUAGCCAUGUCCACAUGGGGGCUUGCACACAGGAUCACUCACAUAUGUACAUGUACCCACCACAAACGUGCAAGCUCCUGCACACAUGCAUGCACACAAACGUGUACACAAGUGUGAGCUCCUACACGCAUACACACACACACGUGUACAUGCACCAAAGCAUGUGUGACCUACAGACAUGCAGAACAUGCACGUGUACACAUACCACAGACACGCGUGUGCAUGCUCCUACACAAUACAUAUGCACAUAUCAUGAACAGCGUAAGUUCCUACACACGGACGUGUGAUACACACAUGCAUGUACAGGUAAGCACACAUGUACAAGCUCCUACAGGCUUGCUCUCACACACGUGUAUGCACAGCAGAGAGACGUAUGAGCUUCUACUGCACACAUGCACACACACACGCACACGUACAUUCACUACAAACGUGCAGCCUCCUGCACACGUGCACAUUCAUGUGUACACCACAAAUGAGUUCCCAGACGUGUAAACACACGUGCACACAUCGUACACAUGUGAGCUCCCACACGUACACACAGAUGCACAUGGACACACCCCAAACACGCACAGGCUCCUACACACAUGCACACACGUGUACACCACAAACGAGCUCCCAGACAUGUAAACACACGUCUCCCACACGUGAGCUCCCACACGUACACAUGCACAUGUACGCACCACAAACACAUGCGCAGGCUCCUGCAGGCGUGAAUACACACAUGCACACACAUAUACACACAUGUGCCACAAACAAGUGCACACUGUCCUGGUGUCCUGCACUGCAUCCUGCCUCCUUGCUGAGGGGCCCCUGUGAGAGGCCUCUGGAUGGGCAUGGGAAGAUGGGCUCCCUGGCCCCCAGCCCAUGCCUCCCUGGGAUGAAGAGUCCCCCUCCUGGCAGAAUGUCUGGGCUUUGCAGAGCAGGCCCCGGGGGUGAAGUCGCAGCUUCACUUACACCAGCUGCUCUGUGAGCAAGGCUUGGUGCCCUGGACAAGGCCCUUCCCCUUUAGGGAGGUCCAGCCUCGCAAGCUGAAACCUCCCCUCGGCUCAGCCCUAUACCAGGCGGCCACAGCAGGACUGGCCACACCCACGCCGCACCUCAUCCGUGCACGCGUCGGAGCACGGCCAGCCUUCCGCCACGAGCCAGCUGGGAAGGGCCGCGGCCGCCUAAAGCCCCAGUCAACCCAGCCUGUGUCUGAGCAGACAGGGCGAACAAGCAGGCCACACCGUCUCGAGGGAGGAGGCCAGAUGCGGCCAGCGUCUCCAACAGGGUGACCAUCCGCUCGGCUUGCUGAGCGUUUAAACAAAUGUUUAGACAGGCUGUGGGGACUCCCCUGAGUUGAGCCUUGGCCAGGGGUCCGGUGCUGUCGCGGGAAACCUCCAGCCUUGUUCUUCAAACCACUCAGCUCAUGUGUUUUGCACUGACUAGUACUGAAUAAUACAACCACUCUUAUUUAAUGUUAGUAUUAUUUAUUUGACAACUCAGUGUCUAACAGCUUGAUAUGCAGGUCCUUGCAUCCUACAUUUCUUUAGGAAGUUACCCAUUUGUAACUUUAAAAACAGGAAAAAUAUCAGUUGGCAAAUGCAAUCUUUUUUUUUUUUAAGCUAAAGGUGGGUGAACUGGAAUGAAAAUCUUUCUGAUGUUGUGUCUAUAAGCAGCCUUGAUGGGAUAUGUUAGAAGUGUCAUGAAAGUGUGAUUCUACUUUUGCAGAAAAAUCUAAAGAUCAAUUUAUAUAGCUUUAUUUUUUACUUUAUCAAAGUAUACAGAAUUUUAAUAUGCAUAUAUUGUGUCUGACUUAAAAUUAUAAUGUCUGCGUCACCAUUUAAAAUGUCUGUUCAUUAUGUAAUGUAAUAAAAGAAGGUCUUCAAAAAUGUAUUUAACAUGAAUGGUAUCCAUAGUUGUCAUCAUCAUAAAUACUGGAGUUUAUUUUUAAAUUAUUAAACAUAGUAGGUGCAUUAACAUAAAUCAGUCUCCACACAGUAACAUUUAACUGAUAAUUCAUUAAUCAGCUUUGAAAAAUUAAAUUGUUAAUUAAACCAAUCUAACAUUUCAGUAAAGUUUAUUUUGUAUGCUUCUGUUUUUAACUUUUAUUUCUGUAGAUAAACUGACUGGAUAAUAUUAUAUUGGACUUUUCUCUAGAUUAUCUAAGCAGGAGACCUGAAUCUGCUUGCAAUAAAGAAUAAAAGUCUGCUUCAGUUUCUUUAUAAAGAAACUCACACAA